AGUUCAAGUUGCCAUAGCUGCGAGUCUGGGGAGAGCACAGUCGGUUGAGUCGCUGCGUUUGGUCAGUUGCACCUUCUGGGUCACUGGUAGCCGCGGGAGCCGGGUGGGGCCUAGGCGAUGAUCCGGCAUUAAGGAGCUGGGAUCAUCCUCCGUCUCAGGUGGUUUGGGGAAAGUGUAGGGGCAACCAAAGAUCAUCGGCUUGACUAGGCCCUUUGCCCUGAACCUCAUGAAGAAAUGAUAGGAGGCAGACAUAUGUGCCUAAAAAGAGCGUUGAGCUCAGAGAAGAGCAACUCGGAGUUUUGGGGGUGUGCUUUGAUUUGUGUACAUCAAUGGCAGAAUCAUCCAGCGAAUCAGAUCACUUCCGCUGUCGUGACCGAUUGAGUCCAUGGGCUGCCAGAUCAACGCACAGGGGAACUCGAAGUCUUCCUACAGUAGAAGUUACCGAGAAGGUCAACACUAUAACAAGUACUUUACAGGAUACCAGUCGGAACCUGCGACAAGUGGACCAGAUGCUUGGACGAUACCGAGAAUACAGUAAUGGACAGGCGGGUGCGAUAGAACAUUUAAAAGAAAGCUUGGAACAAUCAAUCGACCAACUCCGGAGUCAACGUUUAUUGAGAAACUCAGGAGGGAGAAGUAUUUCUGUUACAAGUUUGAGUGCAAGUGACCUUGAUGGUGGCACUGGGUCAGAGCUCCAUCAUUUUCCACCUACCUCACCUCUCAAGGACUAUGGGGAUCCACAGGGUAUUAAACGAAUGAGAUCAAGAACUGGUGUCCGGUUUGUUCAAGAGACUGAUGAUAUGACUCAGCUUCAUGGUUUUCAUCAGUCUCUUCGAGACCUCAGCAGUGAACAAAUUCGCCUUGGAGAUGAUUUCAACAGGGAGCUUUCCAGAAGGAGCCGGUCAGAUGCCGAAACAAAAAGGGCUUUGGAAGAAUUGACUGAAAAACUUAAUGAAGCCCAGAAACAAGAAGUGGUUUCAGAUCGGGUGGAGCGGCGGCUUCAGGAACUGGAGAGAGAGAUGCGCACAGAAAGGGAGCUGGUGGAAAGACGCCAGGAUCAACUGGGACUCAUGUCCCUGCAGCUACAGGAGGCACUAAAGAAACAAGAAGCUAAAGCAGAUGAGCAUGAGGGGGCAAUAAAAAAUAAGCUAAGACAAACUGAAACUGAGAAGAAUCAACUUGAACAGGAAUUGGAGCUAUCUCGAAGGUUAUUGAAUCAAUCAGAAGGCAGCCGAGAAACACUUUUGCAUCAGGUAGAAGAACUGCGUACACAACUUACGAAAGCAGAAGGUGAUCGAAAGGGUUUACAGCAUCAAGUAUCUCAGAUUUCCAAGCAACAGUCAAACUAUCAGGAUGAACAAGGGGAGGACUGGAGAUUUAGGAGAGGGGUUGAGCGGGAAAAACAGGACCUGGAGAAGCAAAUGUCAGAUUUGAGAGUGCAGCUGAACUUCAGCGCAAUGGCAUCUGAGUUAGAGGAAGUGAAACGGUGCAUGGAGAGAAAAGACAAGGAGAAAGCACAUUUGGCAUCACAAGUAGAGAAUUUAACACGUGAACUGGAGAAUGGGGAAAAACAGCAACUGCAGAUGUUGGAUCGACUUAAGGAGAUCCAGAAUCACUUUGACACAUGUGAGGCCGAGCGUAAGCAUGCUGACCUUCAGAUCUCAGAGCUGACUCGCCAUGCGGAGGAUGCAACCAAGCAGGCUGAGCGGUACCUCAGUGAGCUCCAGCAGUCAGAGGCUCUGAAAGAGGAGGCGGAGAAGAGGAGGGAAGACCUGAAACUGAAAGCUCAAGAAUCCAUUAGGCAGUGGAAGCUUAAGCAUAAGAAGUUAGAACGAGCGUUGGAGAAACAAUCUGAAACUGUUGAUGAACUGACAGGCAAGAAUAAUCAGAUUUUAAAAGAAAAGGAUGAAUUGAAAACCCAGCUGUAUGCAGCAUUACAACAAAUAGAGAAUCUUCGAAAGGAAUUGAAUGAUGUCCUAACAAAGCGUGCCCUUCAGGAGGAGGAGCUUCACUCCAAGGAGGAGAAAUUACGUGAUAUUAAGUCUCAUCAAGCUGACCUUGAAUUGGAAGUUAAGAAUUCCCUGGAUACCAUCCAUAGACUGGAGAGCGAAUUGAAAAAGCAGAGUAAGAUCCAAAGCCAGAUGAAAGUUGAGAAAGCUCACUUGGAGGAAGAAAUUGCAGAGCUCAAGAAGAGCCAGGCCCAGGACAAAGCUAAACUUCUUGAGAUGCAAGAGUCCAUCAAGGACCUGAGUGCCAUCCGAGCAGAUCUUGCUAAUAAAUUGGCUGAGGAAGAGAGAGCCAAGAAAGCAGUGCUUAAGGACCUUUCUGACCUCACUGCACAGGCAAAAUCCAGGGAUGAAGAAACAGCUACAAUCAUCACACAGUUAAAGCUGGAACGAGAUGUGCACCAGAGGGAGCUGAAAGAUCUCACAUCAUCAUUGCAGAGUGUGAAAACAAAACACGAACAGAAUAUCCAGGAGCUUAUGAAGCACUUUAAGAAAGAAAAGAGUGAGGCUGAGAAUCAUAUCAGGACUCUGAAGGCUGAAAGUUUAGAAGAGAAGAAUAUGGCUAAAAUUCAUCGUGGUCAGCUGGAGAAGUUGAAAUCACAGUGUGACAGACUGACAGAGGAAUUAACCCAGAAUGAAAAUGAGAACAAAAAACUGAAGCUAAAAUAUCAAUGUUUGAAGGAUCAACUAGAAGAAAGGGAAAAACAUAUAAGCAUUGAAGAGGAGCACUUAAGGAGGAUGGAAGAGGCCAGAUUGCAGCUCAAGGAUCAACUUCUUUGCUUGGAGACUGAACAGGAAUCCAUUCUUGGUGUGAUAGGAAAGGAAAUUGAUGCAGCUUGUAAAACAUUCUCCAAGGACUCAGUGGAGAAAUUAAAAGUUUUUUCAUCUGGUCCUGAUAUACAUUAUGACCCACAUCGCUGGUUAGCAGAAAGCAAGACUAAACUUCAGUGGCUCUGUGAGGAACUGAAAGAGAGAGAAAACAGAGAGAAAAAUCUGCGACACCAGCUGAUGCUCUGCAGACAACAACUCAGGAAUUUGACUGAAAACAAGGAAUCUGAGUUGCAGUGUCUCUUUCAACAGAUAGAAAGGCAGGAGCAGCUUCUGGAUGAAAUACAUCGUGAGAAGAGAGGAAUUUUCCCUAUUAAUACAAGGUUAUAAGCUCCUGAAGCCUUGGCUAAAUCAGACACAUCAUGGCUGUCAUGGUCAUCAGACAUAGGAGAUGUCUGUUGGUUUCUAAACCACAAGAGAAGGUAACAAGUACCUCUGUUUUGGGGGAUUUGGGUAUUGGGAAGGAAAGGGUGAGACAUAUUCUGGUUGCCUACAAAAAGGAUCUUAUAGAAGUUACUUAUUUGUUUUUAUAGAUAGUACCUUAUACUACUUGUUCCUUAUUCAAGGUAAAGGAAUGUAAUUGAAUGGUUAGAGCAUUUACUGGGGAAGUUGUGGUUUUGGGAAACAAAAGCAUUUUCAGAUCACAUUUGUUCAAUUUGUGAUUUCUGAAAGAUCUACCAAUAUAGCUGAAAAAUACCAAAGCCUGAUUAUUCCAUAUAAAUUAAUUAAUUAGAGUUAAUGUUAUUUAAGAGUUUGAGAUCUUUUCUACUGCAUACUUCUUCCGGAGGGAGAUUUUUCUUUCAGGAUUUUAACUUUGUGAAUUACAAUCUUCUCUAAUUAGCAUGAACUUCCUCUUGUACCAGAAUUCUAGCAUAUUAUAAUUCUUGGAGUCAGAAAACUUUUCCUGCUUGGAUAUUAAAUUUUCAUCAGUUAUGGGUCAUUCUUGUUGGGGAUAAUGUGAAAUAGAGGGAACUUGUGUUCUGGAAUAGUUAAUAGAGGUAAAGGUGGAGUAAAUUAUCUGCAGGAAAAAGCACUGGGGGCUGGGCGCAGUGCCUCACCUCUGUAAUCCCAGCACUGUGGGAGGCUGAGGCGGGCAGAUCACUUGAGGUCAGGAGUUCGAGACCGGCCUGGCCAACAUGGUAAAACCCCGUCUCUACUAAAACUACAAAAAUUAGCCGGGCGUCAUGGUGGGCACUUGUAAUCCCAGCUACUUGGGAGGCUGAGGCACGAGAAUCACUUCAACCUGGGAGGUGAAGGUUGCAGUGAGCCGAGAUUGUGCCACUGCACUACAGCCUGGGUGACAAUAGUGAAACUCUGUAUCAAAAAAAAAAAAAAAAUUGGGAAAACAAGAAUGACAAAGAGUAAACCUAAACUCGAGAAUUGAAUUCCAGUUGCCAAUAGAGGGAAAAAACUGAGAAAUAAGACACCCAUGGUGUAUAAUAGGGGCAGAUGGAGGUUUUCCUUGUUCUUUUCAAACACUGACAUAUAUAUAUAUAUAUAUCAUAUAUGUAUAUAUAUAUAUGAUAUAUGUAUAUAUGAUAUAUAUGUAUGAUAUAUAUUAUAUAUAAAUGUAUGAUAUAUAUAUAUAGUAGGUGCCCAAUAAAUAGUUGUUUAGUUAAGUAAGAGUGAAUGAACAAAGGAGCAAACAACAAGGCAAGGAGGCUAGAGUAUACAGUCAGAAGUAGCAUAGGAACUAUCCUGAAAAAGAAAAAAACAUUAAGCCUCUGAUAUAUUUUUGUAACAGCAAGGUAAAACACAUUUAUAAACAUCUUAUUGAAAUUUCAAGAAGAGUGUCUGAGUUUCAGUUGAACGCUAGACAGUGUAUAGAAAUCAGUAGCAAGUCCUACUGUCAACCCCAAAUGUGUAAAUUAUUAUUGGAUAUCUUUUUCUAGUAUGUGUCUUUAUCGUUAAGGUAAACAUAGAAUAAUCUAAAAGCUUUUCAGAGGUUAAUUCCAGAUUUUUACCUUUUCUUUUUCUAUAGAGUCUUGAAUUUCACAAAUAAAAUUUGGUCUUCUCUGUUUCGUUUGUUUUGGGAACCUGUCACCAGUAAUUAGGAGUAAUGAAAAAGGAAGUAACUUACUUAAAACAAUUCCAGAUUGGCUGUUCUUAUAAUGUAUCUAUUUGGAUAAAUUAUUAAUUAUUAUUAUAUUAUUAAGUAUUGAACUAAUUGAGGGCUGAGAUGAUUUUAUUCAACGUCUUAAGUGUCUUUUAUUCCAUAACACACCACAAAUGUUGGGUGGAUAAACAGAUGGAUGAAUGAAUUAUUCUUCAGCAUUCCAAAUUUUAAAGUAGACUUUGGAUCCAGUAAUACCAAAUGAACAAAAGUGUUAGUAAAUAGCAACCCUCUUUAAUUGUGAGCACAUGGUUCCUGAGACUUAAGGGUCAGGAGGAAGCCAAAUAUUUGAAAGCAAUAGCAUACCACAGAACCAAUAACAGUACCCAAUCUCCAUAAGGCUUGUCUGGUUUGUUAUGGUACUCAAUUAUUAAAUGAGGAUAACAGUUUUAAUCUUUUAACUGUUCUGUUUCUACAAGCUAACUUCAACCCCUCUGGGUUCUGUUUUAUGAUGAUGGAUGAUUGUGUUCUGUUCUGCGUAAGUUACUAUUUGCUAAAACUUCCCAGGACACUGUGUAAGGUUUCAGCAAUAGCUUCCAGUUAGCUCUUCAUCUGUUCUCAAGUGACCUGGCAAUCUUGCCCUUCUCUGUGAAGUGGGCUUUGUAUGGUCUCCCAUUGCCUCAGCCAAUUAAGACCUUAAAAUUAGGCUUUGAGGAACCCUGCUCAUGCUUCCAGGAACAUAAUAGCACCACUUUUCAUUGAAGGAGAUGAGAAGUGUUUAAGUUUGGCCAAUGAACAAAGCAAGGAUAAAAACAAGUGCUAAAAUCAUAAUUAGCCCUGAAUAUUUUAAUGCAAAAAGGGUAUCACUUUUUGGACACUGUUCUACCAUUAUGCUAGAUUUCCCUCUAUAAUUUAUGGUUCAAAGUUUUCACUUCUUAUAGAGCCAAUUAAGUUUAUGUAGUAAGACAUUUUGAAAAGGGUACUACACUGUUAUUUUUGAGGCAAAUAACUUCACUACCCUAGAUUUAUGCAUUGAUUAAAACAUUUCUGUUGUCUCCAGCCUGAAUACGAUUCUAGAAUGUGAGUUCUUUAAAGGAUCUUUCUUUGAUUUGGGUGGAAGCGAUGAGCAGGUUUGACAGUGAAGUAUGACACGUUUAUAGGUUUCAUACAUAUUUAAAAGUUGUUGUUAUCAAAUAGUGAUUACCUUAAUGUCUAUUGGUAGUAGUUUGACUCAUUUCACCUUUAAGGAUUCUGGCAUUUUUAUAUUACAUGGGGACUGUCUUUUGCUCACUCUACCAUUCUAGAUUGGCAAUUCUCUUAGUAAUGUUUAAAAGAUAAAGAGGGCCGGGUGCGGUGGCUCAUGGCUGUAAUACCAGCACUUUGGGAGGCCGAGGCGGGCGGAUCACAAGGUCAGGAGAUUAAGACCAUCCUGGCUAACACGGUGAAUCCCCGUCUCUACUAAAAAUACAAAAAAUUAGCCAGGUGUGGUGGCGGGUGCCUGUAGUCCCAGCUACUUGGGAGGCUGAGGCAGGAGAAUGGCGUGAACCCAGGAGGCGGAGCUUGCAGUGAGCCGAGAUCGCGCCAUUGCACUCCAGCCUGGGCGACAGAGCAAGACUCCCGUCUCAAAAAAAAAAAAAAAAAAAAAAGAUAAAGAGUAACCUCUGCUACCAGAUGACAGAAUGCUGUCCUCCUCCUCCUCCUUGUCUUCUUCAUCUCUGUUUGCUUAAUUGUCAGUUGGGUAUCAGAUGAGAAUGGCAAAAUUGGUAUUCCUGUUUUAGUGACAAAAUUAUUUGUAAAGGAAAAAGUUUAAAGAGAAGCUUAUAUAUGAACAUUCUGUUUUAUAGCUGUUAAAUGCUUCAAUAAACAUUUUUUCUUUUCUCAGCUUGAAAACGGCAAAAUAUAUUAAUGAUACAUGUUACAUUUAUAUAUAUAUUAUAUAUACUUAUAUGUGUGCGUCUGUAAUAUAUAAAUAUGUAUACAUAUAUCACAUAUACAUAUGUUAGUGUAUAUGUGUAUGGAUUUUACACACCAAAGAACAGAGAUGAUUUUGUGUAAUCUUAUGUUGAUUGCAUUUUUAGAAUGGGGUCUCACAAUAUUUAGCCAGUCUCUGGAGUCACCACAGUGUUCAGGAACCAGCAUCAGAAAAUACUUAUGAUAUUUGUGUUGUGUUCUACAGUGGUGAUCCUGUUCAUAGCAUGGCAUGACGCUGGGUGUUUCUCAGUAGUGACACUAUGAAUAAUUUGAACUGAACAUCCUUGAUGGUUCAGGCCACCCCCACACACUGAAGGACAUUUGGCUAUCUUCGGCUCCAAAGGAUAAAAUGGAUAUUAGUGUCCAUGCUCUGAAACAAGAAAAAUGCCCUCUUACAUUUCUUUUAGAGAACUACUAAAUGCCUUUCUCACAGCACCAAAAACAUUUUAAUGCAUUUAUUUGUUUUAUUGUUUAUAUCCUUCCGUAAAACUAUAAACCACAUGACAGCAGUAGCCUUGUCUUAAAUAUAUGUGUUCCAUGACUAGCACAGUAUGUGACCCAUAAUCAUUUAAUUUAAUUCAUGUUUAUUCAUCAGACAAAAUGUAAUACUAACUUAAACACUUGCCUAAUUAUUUAUGCUUAUCACUUUGCUCAAACAAUUAUUAAGCAACGUUUUGAAAUCAUUUAACCAGAGAUAUCAUAUCAUGAACUUUAUCCACUUAUUCACGAAUUCACCUGUUUAUUUAUUUAUAUCCUGACUUGUUCGAUAACAGAUUUAUGCAGAGUUGAUUUAAUUUAAAAUGUACAUCAUUAUGGAGCUGUGCUGUAUAAAAGAAACAUAACAAGACAAACAUGAGCUACAUGUAUAGUUUUAAAUUUUCUGAUAAUAAAAUAUUAAAAAGGUAAAAAGAAAGUGAAAUUAAUUUUAAACAUGUAUUUAUGUAACCCAUUAUAUCCUAAAUAUGAUCACUUCAACAUAUAAUCAAUAAGAAAAAUUAUUGACAUAUUUUACAUUUUGUUUUUCAACUGAGAUGCCAAAAUCCGGCAUGUAUUUUACCCUUAGAGCACACCUGAAUUCCAACCAGCCACAUUUCAAAUGUUUAAUAGUCAUAUGUGGCUCAUGGCUAACAUAUUGAACAGAAUAGCCCUAGAGGAUCAUUUAUACUGGCCAUUUUUUGGUCUUAUUCUUUUUAUAAGAGAAUCAUCUGUAGUAUGAUUGCCAGGGUUGUCGAGUUCUCUUUGGGAAGUCCAAGAUGAUGAAUGUAACCUGAAGCUCAUAUUCUCUAAUAUUAAUCCUAUUUAUGAAAAAAUCUUUUAUAUGUAAAAAUUAUUUAAGGGAUCUUACAAUAUAGACAAUUUAUAGCCAUAAUACCAAUAUGUAAGAAGGGAAAUUAAAGAUGUAUAGAAAUUAUUUUCAUAGAUUCUUUGAAUUCUUAAAUUUUCUACGUAACUUUUUAAAAAGGUAGGGAAUAACACGAUUAUGCACCUGGGUAACAGAUAAAGAUAACGAGCAAAUCAGAAAGAUGAACAACUCAAGGAUAUUUAUUUACCUUCAUACUUAGGUUUUCUCUGUGUUGUAUAGAUUGUGGUAGAGAAUUUGGAUGGUUGUUGAAUUUAGAGUUUAUUCUUAAAUUCGUAGUUCAGAUUUUUGGUUUAGAAUAUAGAGGCUAGUAAAUAUUCUGAUCAAGUCAAGGUUAUUUUCCAUUCAGACUAGUUUGUCUGCAUUGCUUAGAUACUUCGUUUCCGCUACCUAGACCAAGUUGUCUAGGUCUAGUUUUUUAUUUUUCAAAACUUAGCACCUGCUGAUGAAUUUGGAAGAACUUUUAUUAGCUACACAGGAAGUAAAUGAGAAGAGACCUAAUAUUUUCUGAGUACCUACCAUAUACCAAGACUUACGUUACAUAAUUUCUCGGACAAUCUUCCAUUUGAUGUGGAUAUUUUUAUUCCUGCUUUAUUAAGGGGGAAGCUGAUACUUACAGAGUUAAAGUAACAAGCCUUGGAUCCAUAGACAAUGAAGAGAUUUCUUUGUAGAAUGUGGCUUGGCUGGGAAUGCAGGGAAUGACACAAUAUCUCCUUAUCCACAUUUAAUCAUGGCCCUUUCCUGUCAUUCACCUCUCAGCAGCUUGCAGUAUUCAUUUUGUGACACUCAACUACUGUCCUUCAACCUUUCAAUGGACCGUGCACUUAGGGAAACAUCCCAGUUUUUUACCAUGAUUAGCAAUAUCCCUUCUGCCCAUUCUCCAGCUUCACCCAUUCUCCCCCUUCAACUUGAGCAUUAUGUUCUGACACAUUUUAUGCUGGCCUUAUUUUUGUUUCUCUUAUAUGCUGAGGCGAUUUCUGCCUCACAGGUGUCACAGUAGUUUUUUUGCCCCCAUCUCGUUUACCCUGUAGCCCCCACCUCCCUAUGCACAUAGCUUUGGCCUCCUCCUUUAGGUCUCAGUUGAAAUGUCACCUCCUCGGAGGGAUCUUGCUCCAUUACCCAAUCUAAGUAGGUCCUUUUCUGUGUUUCUAUCUUUGCAACCUAUUAAUUUACUUCACAGCACUAUAAUUUUAUUUGCAUAUAUAUGCUCAUGGAUUUAUUUAUGUAUUUUCCAUCUUUCCCAUUAGACUCUAAAUUCUCUAAGGCCAGGGACCAUAUCUGUUAUCCUUGCUGCGGUGGUGCACAGUUACUAUGUGUUGAAAACAAAUACUUGUCUUUUAGUUCCUGGAUUGCCAUGAUUUCAUUCCAAAUUGUUCUUCCUGGCUUCAUUUUCUCACUUCUCUGUUUCAUAUUCUAAUAUUGGCAAAUUGUAAUAAAAACUCAUUGGGGUGACUUUUUAGUCCUAUGUCCCCUCUUUCUUCUAAUGAAUUCUGUUUCCUUACCCACAUGGAUAGCUAUAAUCAGGCUUCAUCUGGCCCAGUACUCAUUUUACCACAGGGAUUGUUUAAGAGAUGUGAUCUAGUCUGGGCCUUUCCUUGUCCCUCCUUGAUAAAAAAUUUCAAACUCAAAAUAGGAAAGAUAAUCUUUUUAAAGCUUUGGUCAUGGCACUGAAACUGAUACAGGAAAGGUGAGCCCUAAAAUUGGGGCUUAGCCCAAAGAGUUCUUAGCAUACCCUGGGAAAUAAUUCUAGGACUAGCUGAGCUGGAGGUGUUAGCAGUCUUUUAUUAAAUGGUACUGCUUGGGGUACAGGGCUAAGUUAUAGGCAUUGCACCAUGAGUCCAAAGAAUGGGCUCUUGACAACUGUAUUUAUACUCAUUUAAAGGCACUUUCAAUUACAUGCAAAUUAAGGGGCAGGUUAUUUAGAACUUCCAAGGAAAGGGGCAGUAACUUCUGCAUUGUUGCCAUGGAAUGGGGUGGUAGCUUCUGGGUCAUUGCUAUGGCAUUUGUAAACUGUCAUUGCACUGGUGGGAGUGUCUUAUGCCAAUGAGCAAUGAGGGCACCUAGGAAUCACUUUCAUUGCCAUCUGCCGGUUCCUGCUGAUGGCCUCACUUUACCAAAUCCUGACAGAGUAACAAGUCCAGAAAACAAGUCCUGCCCAUCUCCUUCAUCAAAAGGUUAUAAAACUUUUCUGUCAGAAACCAUAUUUCAUGUGAAGAAGAGAAAACUGUCAGUGAUAGCAGAGAACUAAGCCAACACUCAGAAAAAAACAAAGACGUGAAGCAAAUGAGAGGUUCGCUGGUGUUAAGCCCAUGUACCUAUUUAGCCUGCUUUAUGCCAGUGCCCUUCUUGAUCAGAUACAGCUUUUCAUGCCCUCUUGUUUUGGUUUAAACUGUUGGACUUUGCUGUCUCUCCUCACAGAGUCCUGACAGAUUAAUGUUCUCACAGAAGAGACUGUCAGAAUCCUUUUGUUUUCCUGUGAUAAAUUAAAAAAUACUCAGUAUCACUACAAGAUCACGUGAAACUAAGUUUGUGUAGUUUGGAAAUGGUGGCUCCACUCCUGCAGCUACUGUGUAUUCUGUGUUCCAAAUUCUCACUGUCCUUUCGGUUUCUGAAAACCUAGAGAGGUAAAAUAUCUAUAUGUGAUAUGUGUAUAAUACAAAAUGGUUGUAAACUUGUAGACUGUAUGAUUUAAUUACUAAAACUGUUGUCUUUUUAUGCCAUAUAUAUUUGAGGUCUGUCAUUAAAACUAGUUGUUUAAAUUUUUCUCUGAGUCACCACUUUGAAAGUAGUAUUUAGAAGCAAAUGUUAUGCAACUUUACUUUUGCUGAAAAGAUGAAAUGUGAUGUAUAUACCUAUAAUGUGAAAUCAUCUCUAUAUUAGAGUUAAUGAAUUGACAUUGAUAAUUUAUACAGACUUUCAUUACUACUGAAUCGUGUAAGACUUGUUGGUGAUAUUAUUCACACCUCAUGUCAUUCACACCUUCAACUACAUGAAAAAGUAAGUCUCACCAUUUUGUCUUUGUUGAGUUAUAUGAAAAUGAGGAUCACCAGCCUUGGCAACAUGGAAAAACUUCAUCUCUUCAAAAAACCGAAAACAAACAAACAAAACAUAUAUACACACACAUACACAUACACAUACACAUACACACACACAAGUUAGCUGAGUGUGAUGGUGCAUGCCUAUAGUCAGAGCUACUAGGGAAGCUGAAGUGGGAGAAUCCAUUGAGCCUGAGAGGUCGAGGCUGCAGUGAGCCAUGAUUGUGCCACUGCACUCCAGCCUGGGCAAUAAAGUGAGACCUUGUCUCAAAACAAAAGCAAAAAAAAGAAAAAUAGGAUUAGUAGAUAGAGGCUCUGGGUAUGUGUGAAAUGACAUACUGAGUUAGAUCAAUGAUCUAUUUGAUCUAAUAUUCUGAUUCUGAAAGUGGCACCAAGUAAAUAUUUUGGUAGAAGCACAGUCUUUGCAUUUUAUUUGAUCAUUUUCUGAUAUUAAGUGUGUACUCUAAAUAUCUCAAGUUUUUUUUUAACCUUUGCACCUUAACAAUCUUCUUUAAUUGCUUUUAUAUUUUCAAAAUAUAUAAACCUUCUUUGGGAUGGUGCUCUAUCACAAAUGCCCCCAUUUACCCCUUCUGAUGCUCAUGGAAGAUGUUAUUAUAUUUAAUUUGUUCUAAGUCAGCUACAGCUUCAUUAUCACUCUGAAAACACUGUUCUAGGUAGUCUCUGCCAGCUGAUUUGAAUUGACCCAUGAAGUGAAAUUCAUUUGUUAAUCUCUACAGGAAAUUAGUUUUAAAUGUUAUAGCCUUCUAUUAGAACUGAAGAACUUCUUUUUUUGGGAGUAUUCCAGUAUUUUCAUAUGUUCUUUAAAAUAUUUGAUUUCAAUUCUGCUAGGUGCCGUGAAAGGGACAACUAUAUUAUUUAAAGUAAAUUAUAGCAGAGUCUCUGCCUUUAAGAGCUAACAACUUGUGUGCACUACCAUACCUAUUAGAUUGGACAAUUAUUUCUUUCUAAAUUAACCUUGCCUUUGCCUAAGGUGCUUUGCUUUGCCCCUGUAACUCAAUAAUGAAAUGACAAACAACCCAAUUAAAAAAUGGAUAAAGGUCUGAAUAGACAGUUCUCCAUAGUAGAUGUAAAAUGGCUAAUGAGCACAUGAAAAUGAACACAUUAGCCAUCAGCGAAAUGGAAAGCAAAGCCUCAAAGAGAUACUACUUUAUACUCACCAGGACAGCUAUAAUAAAAAAGAUAGUAACAACUGCUGGCGAAGAUAUAGAGAAAUUGGAACCUGUAUACACUUCUGGUGAGAAUAUGAAAUGGUGCAGCCACUUUGGAAAACAGUCUGUCAGUUACUUAAAAAGUUUAACAUAGAGUUACAUAUAACCUAGAAAUAUGCCCAAGAGAAAUGAAAACAUUUGUCAAGCAAAAACCCGUACACGCAUGUACAUAGCAGCCAAAUGUUUACAACAGCCUUAAGGAUAAACAACCCGAAUGUCCAUCAGCUGACGAAUGGAUAAAUAAAAUAUGGUAUAGUCAUACAGUGGACUAUUAUUUAGCACUAAGAAAUGCAGUAUUAAUAAAUUUUACUACAUGGAUGCACCUUGAAAACUUCAUGCAUAUGAAAAGUCAAUCAUAAGGGAACACAUAUUAUGUGGUUCUGUUUAUAUGAAAUGUCCUGAACAGUUAAAUCUUUAGAUACUGGUGGUUGUACUAUCUAUAUCAUCAUUAAGAAAUAGUGAUUCUGGCUGGUAGAUGAAAUAAAUAACUGCAUGACUACGAGAGUCAACGUGAUGGGUGAUAUGGGAUUUCUUUUUGGGGUAACAACAUGUUUUAAAAUUGAUUGUGGUGAUGGUUGUACACCUCUGUGAAUAUACCAAAAGCCAUCAGGUUGUACACUUUAAAUGGAUAAAUUAUAUGGUGUGUGAAUUUUAUCUCAAUUAAGUUGUUAAAAACUAGGAGUCUCAUUUAAUUUAUUUGGUUCACUUUGCAUAUUUAAUUCAUUGAAUAAUCCUAUCAACUUAAUAAAAUAUAUUUUGAAUCUGUCCCAUUCUGUAAUCUUGGUUUAAAAUCAUCAUUUGCCCAGACAUUAAUGCAGUGGCCUGGUAGCUGCUGGUCUCUCUGUCUCCACUCUUACAUUCAUCCAGUUAUUUAUUUCAUCUGCCAGCAAGUGAUUAUUUUUUACUGAUGAUGAUACAGAAGAUAUUAAUGCUAAUGAAAAAGUGGUUAACACUCAUUUCACAAUUUCUUUUGCCAAGCAUUGUUCUAAGCGCUAUAACAUGCUAACUUACUCAGUCCUUACCACAACUCUUUGAGGUAGGUGCUAUUACUAUCCCCAUUUUAUAGAUGAAGAAACUCAGGUACAGUGAGAUUAGUAAUUCAUCCAAGAUCACUUAACAUGUAAGUGGCUGUUACAUAAAGCAGAUCAAGGCACACUUUUGCUUGAAGAUCUCUAAUGACUUUUACUCCUUUUCCCUCCUUUUUACUAAUUUCCGUUCAAUAAGGCUCAUUUUUUGCCUUGGGUCUUUUGCACUUGCUCCUUCUGUUUGAAAUGCUUUUUUUCCUUCUCAUCUUUCUUGGCUUCCGUGUCACCUCCACAAGGAGGCCUUCUUCAAUAACUUGAACUUGCUCUCACAUUUUCAUACUUCUUCAUUACAUUUAGUAGUGUUUGAAAUUAUCUUAAAAAUUUUAAUUGCAUAUGCGUUCACCCACGGCCUAAUAGAACAAUGCCUAGCAAAUAGCAGGAGCUCGAGAAAACACUUGUUUACUACCUGACUGACUUGUGGGAGAAUAGGAUUUUAUAUAUUUUUCAAAUUAUGGUUGAGGUCUAUUUUCAGAGUAGGAAGACUAUUUGCAUGUCUUGACUAAAGAUUCAUUGUAAACACAAUUUCAUGUUUUUCAGAUUUUAUUAUAAUUCCUUUUUUUUUUCUGAGGCAGGAUCUUGUUCUGUCACCCAGGCUCAAGGGAAGUGGUAUGGUCACAGCUCACUGCAGCCUUGACCUGACAGGCUCAGGUGAUCCUCCCAUCUCAGCCUUCCGAGUAGCUUGGACCAUGGGUGCACACCACCACUCCCAGCUAAUUUUUGUAUUUUUUGCAGAUGUGGAGUUUCACCAUGUUGCCCAGGCUGGUCCCAGACUGCUGGGCUCAAGUGAUCCGCCCACCACGGCCUCCCAAAGUGCUGGGAUUACAGACAUGCCUGGCCUAUAAUUACUUUUAUAAAAAUAAAAUAAUUCCAUGUGAUUGAUGUCUUUCUAAGUGUUGUGGUGCCUUUCAGUUGGUUUAGGGUGGAAAUUGCUUUUUUGAUAAGAUGAUAUUUGAGUGAUUGGACAAUACUGUUAUUCUUAAAUUUUUUCUUUUUUUUUUAAGUCUUGAUCUGCUGCUUUUAGGAUGUGGUUUUAUUAUUGUCGGGUAUGGGAUGUGGGCAGAGAGUAUGAUGGAUGGGGAGAGUAGUUCUUGGUUGUUGGUUUCAUGGGGGCUUUGAAAUGAUAUAGCUGCCGUUAGUGUGGAGACAAUGUGGGAAGUUUGAGGUUUGCCUGUUAGAGAGCUCGGGUAAUUUUCUAGAUCCGUUCUUGUCUGAUAUUAGGUGAUUUUUGGUUGGCAGUGAGAAAUUUUGCAGUGUCAGUCAUGCCUUCUUUUCAUUAGUUGGACAAACACAUACAUGCACUCAUGUGUAUAUUCACAUAUACACAAAAACACACCUUUCUGCUCUAUGUACAUAAUGGCCUUUUAGCCACAGCCUCCCUUCUGUUACUUUUCUUCUGCCUUUCCCAGCUCAGAAUGGUGGUGUUUAUACCCUAAAUGAGAAAAGUAGCCUUAAGUGUGUGUGUAUGUGUGUGUGUGUAUGUGUGUGUGUUUUGCCUUGAAUGGGUGAUGCAACCUAUAUGGACUCAUGAGGAAAUUUUAAAAUUCCAAGUGUAUGCACAACUGGAAUUUUAAUCCAAGCUUUAAUGAAAACAUGGCCUUGUUUAGUGAGUGGAAUAUCAUACAAUUAGAUGUCUGAAAUUUACAUUUUGAUAACUGCUCACUUCUGCUAUAGUGGAAAAGAAUACAAUAUUCAGUAUAUUCUUCCAAGUAGAUUUAUCUUCUCCAAAUAUUAAAAUUGGAUCCCCUGUGCAUCAAUAAUAUUUAAAGAAUUGGAUUAUCCUAACUUUUCACUACUCAGCAGAGUGAGAGAGAGAAACACUAGAUACUGAAAAAUAAAAUAGGAAACUGCAGCAUUGGAUGGCUAGGCUCCAGUUGCUUUUACAUAGUUUCUAAUAACCAAGAUUUUUCAUGCUGCUGACUCUUGAUUCUUUGUGCAAAUAGGCUAGUUGCAGAAUGAUAAAUACAAUUUAUAUAAAAUUAAAAACAAAAUCACUAUCUUUGUUUCCAACCUUCUCUUUUACUCAGUACACGUAAGUAAUGCUGAAUGGAAGUUAUUCUAUUUUUUAAAAAGUUAUGCUUUAAGUGGAUACACAACAAUCAAUCUACUAUGUGCAAAACAGGGGAGAUUAAAGAACAAUAAGACCUUGUCCCUCUCUUAGAAUAUGCUACAGUCCACUAGUGUAGAUACUUACUUUAAUACAGCUUUGUAUGUGUUGCUGUAUAUAUUAAUGAAUUGCUAUAUAUACAGAUAAUGGAGGCACCAUCUCUGCUUGGAUGGGUCAGGGAACUAAGAGAUAGUAUUUAAGUUGGACUCUGAGGGUUAAAUAGGAGUUUGCCAGGUGAAGAAGUAGACAAACAAACAGCCUACACACAAAGUCAUAGAGCUUUGAAAAGGCCAUGCUUGACCAGGAGAUAGGAAGAAAUUCAGGGAGGCAAGAAUAAAACAUUGUUUCCAAAGACAGAAGUCGUAGUAUAUUUCAACAAAUUAGAAGCAGGAGAGGAAGAAUGAGAAAAGAUCACCGCGGAAAAUGUGGUCUGGUAUUAGAUUAUAAAGAGUCUUUUAUAUUAACUACCAGAUGUUUUCCAGUGAGUAAGUGUGGUGUUUCAUUUUAUUUGUAGGAUAAUGCUAGGAGCAAUGGGGAGGCUGCUUUUUACCUGCAAUCCCUCCCACGUAAAGUGCCCUUCUUGAUAACUAUUUUAUUGUUAUUGGUAACAAGGAGCUAUUCAACUUGGUAGUCUGCUUGUGUCUAUCUUGAUUGUCUAUGAUAUGAUUAGAUUCAACUUUUGGUUUUUCUUUUCCAGAUCAGUCAGGGUAUUAUCUAAGGAUGGGUUGAUUCAACCUAGUAUUUUACAGAUUAGAGUUAGUUGGCUUAUGGCAUUUGGAAGAGGCUUCUGGUCCAGCCUAAGCUGGAUAUAAUGGGGAAAUGCAAGCCUCAGGAAAAGUGCAUCCACAGCUACCGACUUGGUUAUUUCUCGUUUCACCAUAUUAACAGUAAAAUAGCUGAUGUGUUUCUGAAAGAGAUAGGCUUAUUGGCAGAACUUUGAGAUGACUACUGUCAUCUCCAGCUGCCUUUGAUGAGGCUGCCAGAGUGCUUGCCUUGGAUCUCCCACUUCAGAGAACCCUUCUACAAAUGGAAUAAAUAGCUGGGUCUACGGAUACAUGGCUACCAACUGAUAGCCACAGUCUCUCUUUUCUAAACCAUGCUCUGGGUACUCAGGACCCCAGAAUACCCCAACCUAGCUGCCAGAGCCCAUGUGCAGGAAAUAUCUGUGGCCCUUCCAUAGGUCAAGUCCUUCCAGGGACAGUGUGAACACCUCUCUGGGCCCAAGUGGUAGCUGAAGUGUAGUUUUCUGAGGGAGUAAUAGGGGUUGGAUGUGUACAGUGUUUCUGGACUCAAUGCUUGAGCCACAUAGGGUGCUGGAUGGAGCCUGGGGUGAGAUGAGAAGGCCACAGGUUGUCAGUUGUACCCUGACAAUAGUAAGGACAGCCUGCCUGGAUGUAAUACUGUUGUUUGAGAGUGCACAAAUUGAAAUGAUUAAGAAGCUCCAGUACAGAACUCUUUAGAGAAUGAAUGUAUUCCUUUUUCUUACAGUUUACCAUCUCAAACUCCUUAUUGUGUUACAGGCAGAUCCGAACAUUAGUGUUCAUAUUGUCAAAUCUUCCUACCCUCAUAUUAAUUUCUUAAAAUUUCAAAUUAAAAAUUUAUUUCUAAAGAUAAUUAUUAAAUUAUGAUAUUAAGUACUAAUUCCCUAGGAUAGCCACAUGUAGUCAUUGAAAUUAGAUUACAAGGAACAAAUUAAGUUCGUAUACUUAUGUUUGUAGCAGAAAAAGAUAAUGAAGAGUGAAUUGGCAUGCAAAUAGUUCAAUAAACACCAUUGAAAUUAUUUUCACUCGAAUUUUUUAUUUUUUACAUUCUUUUUAAUUUAAAAAAAUUUUUAGGUACAUAGUAGGUGUAUAUAUUUAUGGGGUACAUGAGAUACUUUGAUACAAGCAUAUAAUAAACAAUAAUCGCAUUAUGGUAAAUGGGGUAUCCAUUUCUUCAAGCAUUUAUCCUUUGUGUUAUAGAUAAUUCAAUUAUAAUCUUUUAGUUAUUUUUAAAUGUAUACUUAAAUUAUUGAUUAUAGUCACCCUGUUGUGCUAUUAAAUACUAGGUCUUAUUCUUUCUAAAUAUAUAUUUUUGUACCUAUUAGCUAUUCCCACUUUCCCUGCAACCCCCACACUGCUCUUUCCAGCCUCUGGUAACCAGCCUUGUGCUCUCUAUCUACAUGAGUUCUCACUGCUAUUUACUACUGCAAGUAAUAAGAUGUUACAACUGUAAUUUUACAUAUAUUAUCUCUUAUAAGCUAGCCUCUUUCUUAUGUAUGUUUGAAAGGGAAGUGAUUGUUAUUAUGAUGUUAAUUCAUGCUAUGUAAGUAUCAUAUUAGUGUGGUUACACACACACACAGACAUAUAGACACACACACACACACACACACACACACACACACACACAACAUAGUCUUAUAUGUCAGUCUUUAGACCAUAUUCUAAAGGGAGUGGUUUUUUUCUUCAUUGGGAAGAAAAAGGGCAAGUAAUACAGGAUUAUUUUAGAGUAGUUACUGGAAAGGUCUCCUAAGUGAAUUCAUUGUGUUAUAUUGCCUCAGUCCAACAUUUAACUCGAUCUAUAGAAACAAUGAAAACCAUUUCUUGAGAACAGAAAAACAAACAAAAUUAGAUAGCUUCUCAUAUAAGCCAAAAAGCUGCUUUGUUUUUAGCUGCUAUACUGUUUCUCUUAAGAGGAUGGAUGUUCAUUGUAUUUGAUAAGUUAUCAAGAUUUACUUUAAUGUUCCAGAGUGUGCAAGUUAAUGAUUUCAGACGAUAAUUUUUUGUAUCACUUUAGAGGAAACUAUUGGACAAUUUGAAUAUCAGAUGGUUUAUUUCCAAAAUCAUAUUAUGGUCUUGAAAUUGUUUUGGGUUAAUGUUUUGCUGGAGUUUGUGCAUUGUCAGUUCUUGUUAUUCAAAAUCACGUUUGAUUUUUUUAUUCUGUUCAAGAAAAUAUCCAAUUAAAGUCAAUAGAAUGCACAUACUAUAAAAUUCCUGACCAGUUAGUAGACCAUUUGGACAGGUUGAUGUAGGAUCAAACAAAAAGGGGUUAAUUUGAUUGUCAUGUUUUAGGAGAACUUUAAAUUAUAAGUCACUUGCUUUAUAUUCAGUUGUAUAGUACUUAAUGAAAGUAUUUAAAUAAAGUAAAUCUAUUUCUUUAAUACUUAUAAAUAUCCAGAGUAACUUGUGGAAGAAUUUAAGAAAUUAUGUUUUAUGAAUUUGAUAAGUUACUCUUAUGUUUUCACAAUAUAUUUUAAUUAUUUUCAUAGGUGGUGAGACGUGUAUGAAUUCAGUUGACACCAAAGUAGAUGCAAAUAAAUAUAUUUUGUUUCUUUUUCAAGAGUUAAAUCUGAAUUUCUUAACUUUUCUUCUCUCCUAUACUCAAUAUAUCAUACUGUAAUUGUGAUAUUUCUCAUGAGAAAACAGUCAAUAAGAUCUCUUAUCUAGUAACAUAUAUCUAGUGAGGGAGAUGUGAACAACAGAUAACUGGCCUCUGUUCUAAACCCUUUGGUAAUGGGAAUUAUGUUUGCACCAAUUUAUGGCAUGAUUUCAUUAUUAGAUUGUUAAUACAUGUUCUUAACAAAUAGCAGUAUUUUGCAAAUAGUUGUAGGUAUAGAAUAUCUGUUUGUAUCCUCAUAUCCUCAUAUCCUCAAAAGGUCCAGGGUACAAAAACAGGGUACAAAACAAAUUGUUGUGCUGGCUUUUUUUUUUUAAGACAAUUCCUUUUUUGGCUACUCUCUUAUUCUUAAUUUUUCUCCUAGUUUUUAGAUUUGUUAUAGUGAUACAAUAAUUUACUCAUUUGCCAUUUCAUAAGCAAACUAUCAAAAUUGUUAAUAAUGAAAACUGAACCAAUCAGAAAAAAACCUACUGAUAAUAUGCAAAAGAAGACCCCAUUCAUUUAUUGAUAAAGAAAAUAAACUACCUAGGUGUAAUUAGCCUUAACAAGAAAUGUCAAAACCCAUAUGAGGAAAACUGAAAUACACAUGUGAAAGAUAUAGAAGUAUACUGGAAGAAAUGAAAGGCAUAUUAGUUCCUUGAAUAGGAAGACUCAAACAUCAUAAAAUAUCAUUUAUUUCUAAGUUAUUUUUUAUAUGUAAAGCAGUCUUAAUGCACAUACAGUCAGAUUUUUUUGUAUUAAAUGUAUCUUGAAAAGUUGAUUAUAAAAUUCAUUUGGAAGAAUGAAAAGGCAAGAAUAUCCAGCAAAAUGCUGAAAAAGAAGAGAAGUGAAAAGGUUAAUGCUACCAGAUAUUAAAACAUAAUUUAAAACUGGCUGGGUGCAGUGGCUCAUGCCUGUAAUCCCACCACUUUGGGAGCCUGAGGCAGAUGGAUCACCUGAGGUCAGGAGUUCGAGACCAGCCUGGCCAACAUAGUGAAACCCCAUCUGUACUAAAAAUACAAAAUUAGCUGGGCAUGGUGGCAGGCACCUGUAAUCCCAGCUACUCGGGAGGCUGAGACAGGAGAAUCACUUGAACCCGGGAAGCAGAGUUUGCAGUGGCUGAGGUCAUGCCAUUGCACGUCAGCCUGGAUGACAAGAGCGAAACUCCGUCUCAAAAAAAAAACAAAAACCCUAAAAAUAAUAGUAAUAAUAUAAAACUUAGAGUUUUAUUUUAUUAUUUUAUUUAUUUAUAUUUUUAUUUUUUUAUUACAGGCGUGAGCUACCACACCCAGCCUAAAACUUACAAUUUUAAAAAAAUUGACUAGAAGGACUACUAGAACAGAAUAGAAAAUCUCCCCAAAUAGGCCCAAAUACUGAAGGAAAUUUAGUUUACAAUGAAGCUAGAAUUUGAAAUCAGUGGAGAUGGAUAUACCUUUUAAUAAAUGUGCUGUAACAACUGGAUAUUUAUAUGGAAAAAUAUAAAAAUUAGAUCUAUUCUGACACCAUUCAUCAGUAUAAUUUUAAAUGGGCCAGAAGUUUAAUGUAAAAACUUUAAUUAUUCAAAUACUAUAGGAAGCAAAUGCUUUUAUAAUGUGGCUACAGAUUAAAUUUACAUGACUACUAGCUAAAAUUCAGAGGCAAUCAGGGAGUAAAGAUUGACUAAUUUGAUUGCAUAGCAGUUUUUUAAAAUGGCAAAACAUUUUCACCAUAAGCAAAAUAAAAAACAAAUAAUGGGUGCAGCACACCAGCAUGGCACAUGGAUACAUAUGUAACUAACCUGCACAUUGUGCACAUGUACCCUAAAACUUAAAGUAUAAUAAUAAUAAAAUAAAAAAUGGAAAAUAAUCGAAAAAAAAUGGAAACAGUAUUUGCAAGUCUUAUCACAGACAAGAGGUGAUAUUCCCAUAUCCCUAAUAUAUAAACAACUUAUUAAAAAAUCCAAAUGCAUGACAAUGUCUGUGAGGCUGGGGACUGUGAGGAAAUAGACCCUUUCAAACAUUGCUUGUAGGAAUGCAAAAAUGGUACAAUCCUCUGAAAGUGACUCAGAAUCUAGUUAAUUUUCAUAAGCAUUUUUUGACUCUUCAAUUCCCCUUUUAGGAAUGUAUAUCAAAAGAUACAGUGAAAACAAUACAAAAUUCCAGUAAAUAACGCUUCUUAUGCGGCACUAUCUUUAAUAGCAAAUACUGGAAAUAACCAAAUGUCCAUAGGGGACGUGAAGAAAAAAAAUGGUACAUCCAGAAUAUGUAGUAGUAUGCAGCAAUGAAAAGGAAUGCAAAUAUUUCUACAUCAAAUGGCACAUUAAUCUACAGGAUAUACCAUAAUAUGAGAUAAAUGACUUAUAUGCUACUAUUUAAGAAAUGAGGGUACUAUACCUAUUUUUGACUUUAGAACAAUGUAAAUAUUUUAUGUAAUUUUCAAACAAAGUUAAUGUUGAACAGAAGAAAUUUCAAGAUAGCUAUAUAUCCUUAGUGGGUUAUACCUUAAUGACAAAAAGGAUUGCAAAAAAAUUAGAUUUUUUAAAAAACAUAUUUUCUUGUGGUAUUGGUGGUAUUUUAGACAAUUAUGUUUGUCUUGAGGAAUAAAUCAAAUGAUUAAUUAUAUAGGUAUUAUUGAAAACUGAGAUUUAUGGAUAGAUUACUAAGGUUAAGUAAAAAUCAUGUAGUAGUAAAUUUGAAUUGUAUCAGUAUGACCUCAUGUUGGAUUUUAUCUUAAACAAAUUUUGGGUUUGAUGUGUAUGUACAGCUUCACAAACAGAGACCAGUGCAGUUAUCAAUGAGUGUAUCUAUAGCACCAAGAUUAUGAUAUUUAAAUACCAUUUGCCAUGAAAAAAGUCCCCAAAACUCCUUGGAGAAUUGGUUGGUUCUGAUCAGGUAUAAAUAUUUACGUGGUAAACUUGGAAAGUCUUAGUAUUUCAGAAGCCAAGGAAGCUAUCAAAAACUAGGCUCACCCUCCUCAGGCAGCUCUAGCACGGGCCAGUGGGAUAUCCAGCAGAUAAACCAAGCUGAACAAAACAACACUACAAGGUCUCUGAAAAUUUAACUGUCAUUAGAACCAUAGCCUACAAAAGUAGGUGAAGACCCACAUGAUAAACCUAACCAGAGUGAUUGCCUGCUUAAAUAAAACAUUUAAAUAGAACCCACAGUCUCAUAACAUAACAGACAAUGUCUAGAAUAUGAUUUUAAAAAUCACUUGCCAUACCAAGAAUCAUGAGAAUAAAUAAAACAAACAUCUGCCACCAACAUUGAAAUAAAUCGGGUACUGGAAAUAGAUUUAAAGAAGGAAUCAUAAAAAUUCCUGAACAAUCUCUGUCACAAAUGGAUAAUCUCAACAAAGAAAUAAAAGUUAUGCAAAAGUACCAAAUGGAUGUUAUGGAAAUGAGAAAUACAACAACAGAAAGAAAAAUAUCACGGAUGGGUUGAGUAGUAGAAUGAGAUAACAGAAGAUAGAAUCAACAAACUGGAAGAAAGAAUUCACCUCAUUUGAACAAUAGGGAGAAAAUAAAUUGAAAAAGAAGAAAAAA